GGACACUGCCCUGGAGAGUGACCCGAUGCAGCAGCUGCACAGGCCAUCCUCCCCACCCACGCACCCCUGCUGAGAACAUGUCUGUGAGGUUCAGGGUGGGCAGAGAGGAGAAUGCCCAGUGGUGGCUCUUGUACCUCCUGGUGCCGGCCCUGUUCUGCAGGGCAGGAGGCUCCAUUCCCAUCCCUCAGAAGUUAUUUGGGGAGGUGACUUCCCCUCUGUUCCCCAAGCCUUACCCCAACAACUUUGAAACAACCACUGUGAUCACAGUCCCCACGGGAUACAGGGUGAAGCUCGUCUUCCAGCAGUUUGACCUGGAGCCUUCUGAAGGCUGCUUCUAUGAUUAUGUCAAGAUCUCUGCUGAUAAGAAAAGCCUGGGGAGGUUCUGUGGGCAACUGGGUUCUCCACUGGGCAACCCCCCGGGAAAGAAGGAAUUUAUGUCCCAAGGGAACAAGAUGCUGCUGACCUUCCACACAGACUUCUCCAACGAGGAGAAUGGGACCAUCAUGUUCUACAAGGGCUUCCUGGCCUACUACCAAGCUGUGGACCUUGAUGAAUGUGCUUCCCGGAGCAAAUCAGGGGAGGAGGAUCCCCAGCCCCAGUGCCAGCACCUGUGUCACAACUACGUUGGAGGCUACUUCUGUUCCUGCCGUCCAGGCUAUGAGCUUCAGGAAGACAGGCAUUCCUGCCAGGCUGAGUGCAGCAGCGAGCUGUACACGGAGGCAUCAGGCUACAUCUCCAGCCUGGAGUACCCUCGGUCCUACCCCCCUGACCUGCGCUGCAACUACAGCAUCCGGGUGGAGCGGGGCCUCACCCUGCACCUCAAGUUCCUGGAGCCUUUUGAUAUUGAUGACCACCAGCAAGUACACUGCCCCUAUGACCAGCUACAGAUCUAUGCCAACGGGAAGAACAUUGGCGAGUUCUGUGGGAAGCAAAGGCCCCCCGACCUCGACACCAGCAGCAAUGCUGUGGAUCUGCUGUUCUUCACAGAUGAGUCGGGGGACAGCCGGGGCUGGAAGCUGCGCUACACCACCGAGAUCAUCAAGUGCCCCCAGCCCAAGACCCUAGACGAGUUCACCAUCAUCCAGAACCUGCAGCCUCAGUACCAGUUCCGUGACUACUUCAUUGCUACCUGCAAGCAAGGCUACCAGCUCAUAGAGGGGAACCAGGUGCUGCAUUCCUUCACAGCUGUCUGCCAGGAUGAUGGCACGUGGCAUCGUGCCAUGCCCAGAUGCAAGAUCAAGGACUGUGGGCAGCCCCGAAACCUGCCUAAUGGUGACUUCCGUUACACCACCACAAUGGGAGUGAACACCUACAAGGCCCGUAUCCAGUACUACUGCCAUGAGCCAUAUUACAAGAUGCAGACCAGAGCUGGCAGCAGGGAGUCUGAGCAAGGGGUGUACACCUGCACAGCACAGGGCAUUUGGAAGAAUGAACAGAAGGGAGAGAAGAUUCCUCGGUGCUUGCCAGUGUGUGGGAAGCCCGUGAACCCCGUGGAACAGAGGCAGCGCAUCAUCGGAGGGCAAAAAGCCAAGAUGGGCAACUUCCCCUGGCAGGUGUUCACCAACAUCCACGGGCGCGGGGGCGGGGCCCUGCUGGGCGACCGCUGGAUCCUCACAGCUGCCCACACCCUGUAUCCCAAGGAACACGAAGCGCAAAGCAACGCCUCUUUGGAUGUGUUCCUGGGCCACACAAAUGUGGAAGAGCUCAUGAAGCUAGGAAAUCACCCCAUCCGCAGGGUCAGCGUCCACCCGGACUACCGUCAGGAUGAGUCCUACAAUUUUGAGGGGGACAUCGCCCUGCUGGAGCUGGAAAAUAGUGUCACCCUGGGUCCCAACCUCCUCCCCAUCUGCCUCCCUGACAACGAUACCUUCUACGACCUGGGCUUGAUGGGCUAUGUCAGUGGCUUCGGGGUCAUGGAGGAGAAGAUUGCUCAUGACCUCAGGUUUGUCCGUCUGCCCGUAGCUAAUCCACAGGCCUGUGAGAACUGGCUCCGGGGAAAGAAUAGGAUGGAUGUGUUCUCUCAAAACAUGUUCUGUGCUGGACACCCAUCUCUAAAGCAGGACGCCUGCCAGGGGGAUAGUGGGGGCGUUUUUGCAGUAAGGGACCCGAACACUGAUCGCUGGGUGGCCACGGGCAUCGUGUCCUGGGGCAUCGGGUGCAGCAGGGGCUAUGGCUUCUACACCAAAGUGCUCAACUACGUGGACUGGAUCAAGAAAGAGAUGGAGGAGGAGGACUGAGCCCAGAAUUCACUAGGUUCGAAUCCAGAGAGCAGUGUGGAAAAAAAAAAACAAAAAACAACUGACCAGUUGUUGAUAACCACUAAGAGUCUCUAUUAAAAUUACUGAUGCAGAAAGACCGUGUGUGAAAUUCUCUUUCCUGUAGUCCCAUUGAUGUACUUUACCUGAAACAACCCAAAGGGCCCCUUUCUUUCUUCUGAGGAUUGCAGAGGAUAUAGUUAUCAAUCUCUAGUUGUCACUUUCCUCUUCCACUUUGAUACCAUUGGGUCAUUGAAUAUAACUUUUUCCAAAUAAAGUUUUAUGAGAAAUGCCA